AGCUCACAAAUCAAGCCUCAGAAAGAGCUGACAUCCUAGCUCUUCCCGGAAAAACUCGAAUGUCGCCCUGCCGUUCCUGGGGUUGGUGACAGGUCUGGUCAUCGCACGGCGGCAGCUCCUCACCUGGAUUUAGAAGAGCUGGCGUCCCCGCCCGCCCAAGCCUUUAAACUCUCGUCUGCCAGAACCCGCCAACUCUCCAGGCUUAGGGCCAGUUUCCGCGAUUCUAAGAGUAAUUGCGUGGGCACCUGUGCUGGGGCCAGGCGCAAAGAAGGGAGUUGGUCUGCGCGAAGAUCGUCAACCUGCUAACAGACCGCACAUGCACUUUGCACCGACCAUCUACGUCUCAGUCUGGAGGUUGCGCACUUUGGCUGCUGACGCGCUGGUGGUGCCUAUUAAUCAUUUACCAGUCCAGAGCCGCGCCAGUUAAUGGCUGUGCCGUGCGGUGCUCCCACAUCCUGGCCUCUCCUCUCCACGGUCGCCUGUGCCCGGGCACCCCGGAGCUGCAAACUGCAGAGCCCAGGCAACCGCUGGGCUGUGCGCCCCGCCGGCGCCGGUAGGAGCCGCGCUCCCCGCAGCGGUUGCGCUCUACCCGGAGGCGCUGGGCGGCUGUGGGCUGCAGGCAAGCGGUCGGGUGGGGAGGGAGGGCGCAGGCGGCGGGUGCGCGAGGAGAAAGCCCCAGCCCUGGCAGCCCCACUGGCCCCCCUCAGCUGGGAUGUUCCCCAAUGGCACCGCCUCCUCUCCUUCCUCCUCUCCUAGCCCCAGCCCGGGCAGCUGCGGCGAAGGCGGCGGCAGCAGGGGCCCCGGGGCCGGCGCUGCGGACGGCAUGGAGGAGCCAGGGCGAAAUGCGUCCCAGAACGGGACCUUGAGCGAGGGCCAGGGCAGCGCCAUCCUGAUCUCUUUCAUCUACUCCGUGGUGUGCCUGGUGGGGCUGUGUGGGAACUCUAUGGUCAUCUACGUGAUCCUGCGCUAUGCCAAGAUGAAGACGGCCACCAACAUCUACAUCCUAAAUCUGGCCAUUGCUGAUGAGCUGCUCAUGCUCAGCGUGCCCUUCCUAGUCACCUCCACGUUGUUGCGCCACUGGCCCUUCGGUGCGCUGCUCUGCCGCCUCGUGCUCAGCGUGGACGCGGUCAACAUGUUCACCAGCAUCUACUGUCUGACUGUGCUCAGCGUGGACCGCUACGUGGCCGUGGUGCAUCCCAUCAAGGCGGCCCGCUACCGCCGGCCCACCGUGGCCAAGGUAGUAAACCUGGGCGUGUGGGUGCUAUCGCUGCUCGUCAUCCUGCCCAUCGUGGUCUUCUCUCGCACCGCGGCCAACAGCGACGGCACGGUGGCUUGCAACAUGCUCAUGCCAGAGCCCGCUCAACGCUGGCUGGUGGGCUUCGUGUUGUACACAUUUCUCAUGGGCUUCCUGCUGCCCGUGGGGGCUAUCUGCCUGUGCUACGUGCUCAUCAUUGCUAAGAUGCGCAUGGUGGCCCUCAAGGCCGGCUGGCAGCAGCGCAAGCGCUCGGAGCGCAAGAUCACCUUAAUGGUGAUGAUGGUGGUGAUGGUGUUUGUCAUCUGCUGGAUGCCUUUCUACGUGGUGCAGCUGGUCAACGUGUUUGCUGAGCAGGACGACGCCACGGUGAGUCAGCUGUCGGUCAUCCUCGGCUAUGCCAACAGCUGCGCCAACCCCAUCCUCUAUGGCUUUCUCUCAGACAACUUCAAGCGCUCUUUCCAACGCAUCCUAUGCCUCAGCUGGAUGGACAACGCCGCGGAGGAGCCGGUUGACUAUUACGCCACCGCGCUCAAGAGCCGUGCCUACAGUGUGGAAGACUUCCAACCUGAGAACCUGGAGUCCGGCGGCGUCUUCCGUAAUGGCACCUGCACGUCCCGGAUCACGACGCUCUGAGCCCGGGCCACGCAGGGGCUCUGAGCCCGGGCCACGCAGGGGCCCUGAGCCAAAAGAGGGGGAGAAUGAGAAGGGAAGGCCGGGUGCGAAAGGGACGGUAUCCAGGGCGCCAGGGUGCUGUCGGGAUAACGUGGGGCUAGGACACUGACAGCCUUUGAUGGAGGAACCCAAGAAAGGCGCGCGACAAUGGUAGAAGUGAGAGCUUUGCUUAUAAACUGGGAAGGCUUUCAGGCUACCUUUUUCUGGGUCUCCCACUUUCUGUUCCUUCCUCCACUGCGCUUACUCCUCUGACCCUCCUUCUAUUUUCCCUACCCUGCAACUUCUAUCCUUUCUUCCGCACCGUCCCGCCAGUGCAGAUCACGAACUCAUUAACAACUCAUUCUGAUCCUCAGCCCCUCCAGUCGUUAUUUCUGUUUGUUUAAGCUGAGCCACGGAUACCGCCACGGGUUUCCCUCGGCGUUAGUCCCUAGCCGCGCGGGGCCGCUGUCCAGGUUCUGUCUGGUGCCCCUACUGGAGUCCCGGGAAUGACCGCUCUCCCUUUGCGCAGCCCUACCUUAAGGAAAGUUGGACUUGAGAAAGAUCUAAGCAGCUGGUCUUUUCUCCUACUCUUGGGUGAAGGUGCAUCUUUCCCUGCCCUCCCCUGUCCCCCUCUCGCCGCCCGCCCGCCACCACCACUCUCACUCCACCCAGAGUAGAGCCAGGUGCUUAGUAAAAUAGGUCCCGCGCUUCGAACUCCAGGCUUUCUGGAGUUCCCACCCAAGCCCUCCUUUGGAGCAAAGAAGGAGCUGAGAACAAGCCGAAUGAGGAGUUUUUAUAAGAUUGCGGGGUCGGAGUGUGGGCGCGUAAUAGGAAUCACCCUCCUACUGCGCGUUUUCAAAGACCAAGCGCUGGGCGCUCCCGGGCCGCGCGUCUGCGUUAGGCAGGGCAGGGUAGUGCAGGGCACACCUUCCCCGGGGUUCGGGGUUCGGGGUUCGGUUGCAGGGCUGCAGCCCGCCUUGGCUUUCUCCCUCACCCAAGUUUCCGGAGGAGCCGACCUAAAAGUAACAAUAGAUAAGGUUUCCUGCUCCAGUGUAUCUCAAAAGACCGGGCGCCAGGGGCGGGGGACCUAGGGCGACGUCUUCAGAGUCCGCCAGUGUUGGCGGUGUCGCCGCAACCUGCAGGCUCCCGAGUGGGGCCUGCCUGGUCUCUAGAGGGUUGCUGCCUUUCAAGCGGUGCCUAAGAAGUUAUUUUCUUGUUUAACAUAUAUAUUUAUUAAUUUAUUUGUCGUGUUGGAAAAUGUGUCUCUGCUUUCCUUUUCUCUGCUUGCCUAGCCCCAGGUCUUUUCUUUGGGACCCUGGGGGCGGGCAUGGAAGUGGAAGUAGGGGCAAGCUCUUGCCCCACUCCCUGGCCAUCUCAACGCCUCUCCUCAAUGCUGGGCCCUCUUAUCUCAUCCUUUCCUCUAGCUUUUCUAUUUUUGAUUGUGUUGAGUGAAGUUUGGAGAUUUUUCAUACUUUUCUUACUAUAGUCUCUUGUUUGUCUUAUUAGGAUAAUACAUAAAUGAUAAUGUGGGUUAUCCUCCUCUCCAUGCACAGUGGAAAGUCCUGAACUCCUGGCUUUCCAGGAGACAUAUAUAGGGGAACAUCACCCUAUAUAUAAUUUGAGUGUAUAUAUAUUUAUAUAUAUGAUGUGGACAUAUGUAUACUUAUCUUGCUCCAUUGUCAUGAGUCCAUGAGUCUAAGUAUAGCCACUGAUGGUGACAGGUGUGAGUCUGGCUGGAACACUUUCAGUUUCAGGAGUGCAAGCAGCACUCAAACCUGGAGCUGAGGAAUCUAAUUCAGACAGAGACUUUAAUCACUGCUGAAGAUGCCCCUGCUCCCUCUGGGUUCCAGCAGAGGUGAUUCUUACAUAUGAUCCAGUUAACAUCAUCACUUUUUUUGAGGACAUUGAAAGUGAAAUAAUUUGUGUCUGUGUUUAAUAUUACCAACUACAUUGGAAGCCUGAGCAGGGCGAGGACCAAUAAUUUUAAUUAUUUAUAUUUCCUGUAUUGCUUUAGUAUGCUGGCUUGUACAUAGUAGGCACUAAAUACAUGUUUGUUGGUUGAUUGUUUAAGCCAGAGUGUAUUACAACAAUCUGGAGAUACUAAAUCUGGGGUUCUCAGGUUCACUCAUUGACAUGAUAUACAAUGGUUAAAAUCACUAUUGAAAAAUACGUUUUGUGUAUAUUUGCUUCAACAACUUUGUGCUUUCCUGAAAGCAGUAACCAAGAGUUAAGAUAUCCCUAAUGUUUUGCUUAAACUAAUGAACAAAUAUGCUUUGGGUCAUAAAUCAGAAAGUUUAGAUCUGUCCCUUAAUAAAAAUAUAUAUUACUACUCCUUUGGAAAAUAGAUUUUUAAUGGUUAAGAACUGUGAAAUUUACAAAUCAAAAUCUUAAUCAUUAUCCUUCUAAGAGGAUACAAAUUUAGUGCUCUUAACUUGUUACCAUUGUAAUAUUAACUAAAUAAACAGAUGUAUUAUGCUGUUGCAA